AGAAGAGAUUUGUCACUGAUGCUAAUGCAUGCUGCUCUGCAGGGGACCACUCUCCCUCGAAGCUCCCCAUAGCUGCUCUCAGUUUUAUGGAUCUGCUCUACUCAAAGCCUUGCAGAAGGGGCAGGGGAUGCCCAGGUUAACCCCCGCACGUACAAAGGUGGAGCAGUUUUCAUGCAUAGCUGGGACGAAGAACACUGGAAAGAGAAAGAAAAAUUUUCCGAGCUACUGCUAAGCCAGAAAAGCUCAGCUCUCAAACGGACUAUCUCCUGAGACGUCACACAGCUGGGAACUGAUCCGCAAUACAGCAAAGGUGUGUGGAUGUCUCCUAGAUCUUGACUUGCUCCUGAGGAAAUAUUGUGUGACUGAGUUUCCUGUUAUACUGCUCUCCAAUCCAUCAUGAACCAGCCAGAGUCUGCCAACGAUCCUGAACCCCUGUGUGCAGUGUGUGGCCAAGCCCACUCCUUGGAGGAAAACCACUUCUACAGCUAUCCAGAGGAAGUGGAUGAUGACCUCAUCUGCCACAUCUGCCUGCAGGCUUUGCUGGACCCCCUGGACACUCCGUGUGGACACACCUACUGCACCCUCUGCCUCACCAACUUCCUGGUGGAGAAGGACUUCUGUCCCAUGGACCGCAAGCCUCUGGUUCUGCAGCACUGCAAGAAGUCCAGCAUCCUGGUCAACAAACUCCUCAACAAGCUACUGGUGACCUGCCCAUUCAGGGAGCACUGCACCCAGGUGUUGCAGCGCUGUGACCUCGAGCAUCACUUUCAAACCAGCUGUAAAGGUGCCUCCCACUACGGCCUGACCAAAGAUAGGAAGAGGCGCUCACAAGAUGGCUGUCCAGACGGCUGUGCGAGCCUCACAGCCACGGCUCCCUCCCCAGAGGUUUCUGCAGCUGCCACCAUCUCCUUAAUGACAGACGAGCCUGGCCUAGACAACCCUGCCUACGUGUCCUCGGCAGAGGACGGGCAGCCAGCAAUCAGCCCAGUGGACUCUGGCCGGAGCAACCGAACUAGGGCACGGCCCUUUGAGAGAUCCACUAUUAGAAGCAGAUCAUUUAAAAAAAUAAAUCGAGCUUUGAGUGUUCUUCGAAGGACAAAGAGCGGGAGUGCAGUUGCCAACCAUGCCGACCAGGGCAGGGAAAAUUCUGAAAACACCACUGCCCCUGAAGUCUUUCCAAGGUUGUACCACCUGAUUCCAGAUGGUGAAAUUACCAGCAUCAAGAUCAAUCGAGUAGAUCCCAGUGAAAGCCUCUCUAUUAGGCUGGUGGGAGGUAGCGAAACCCCACUGGUCCAUAUCAUUAUCCAACACAUUUAUCGUGAUGGGGUGAUCGCCAGAGACGGCCGGCUACUGCCAGGAGACAUCAUUCUAAAGGUCAACGGGAUGGACAUCAGCAAUGUCCCUCACAACUACGCUGUGCGUCUCCUGCGGCAGCCCUGCCAGGUGCUGUGGCUGACUGUGAUGCGUGAACAGAAGUUCCGCAGCAGGAACAAUGGACAGGCCCCGGAUGCCUACAGACCCCGAGAUGACAGCUUUCAUGUGAUUCUCAACAAAAGUAGCCCCGAGGAGCAGCUUGGAAUAAAACUGGUGCGCAAGGUGGAUGAGCCUGGGGUUUUCAUCUUCAAUGUGCUGGAUGGCGGUGUGGCAUAUCGACAUGGUCAGCUUGAGGAGAAUGACCGUGUGUUAGCCAUCAAUGGACAUGAUCUUCGAUAUGGCAGCCCAGAAAGUGCGGCUCAUCUGAUUCAGGCCAGUGAAAGACGUGUUCACCUCGUCGUGUCCCGCCAGGUUCGGCAGCGGAGCCCUGACAUCUUUCAGGAAGCCGGCUGGAACAGCAAUGGCAGCUGGUCCCCAGGGCCAGGGGAGAGGAGCAACACUCCCAAGCCCCUCCAUCCUACAAUUACUUGUCAUGAGAAGGUGGUAAAUAUCCAAAAAGACCCCGGUGAAUCUCUCGGCAUGACCGUCGCAGGGGGAGCAUCACAUAGAGAAUGGGAUUUGCCUAUCUAUGUCAUCAGUGUUGAGCCCGGAGGAGUCAUAAGCAGAGAUGGAAGAAUAAAAACAGGUGACAUUUUGUUGAAUGUGGAUGGGGUCGAACUGACAGAGGUCAGCCGGAGUGAGGCAGUGGCAUUAUUGAAAAGAACAUCAUCCUCGAUAGUACUCAAAGCUUUGGAAGUCAAAGAGUAUGAGCCCCAGGAAGACUGCAGCAGCCCAGCAGCCCUGGACUCCAACCACAACAUGGCCCCACCCAGUGACUGGUCCCCAUCCUGGGUCAUGUGGCUGGAAUUACCACGGUGCUUGUAUAACUGUAAAGAUAUUGUAUUACGAAGAAACACAGCUGGAAGUCUGGGCUUCUGCAUUGUAGGAGGUUAUGAAGAAUACAAUGGAAACAAACCUUUUUUCAUCAAAUCCAUUGUUGAAGGAACACCAGCAUACAAUGAUGGAAGAAUUAGAUGUGGUGAUAUUCUUCUUGCUGUCAAUGGUAGAAGUACAUCAGGAAUGAUACAUGCUUGCUUGGCAAGACUGCUGAAAGAACUUAAAGGAAGAAUUACUCUAACUAUUGUUUCUUGGCCUGGCACUUUUUUAUAGAAUCAAUGAUGGGUCAGAGGAAAACAGAAAAAUCACAAAUAGGCUAAGAAGUUGAAACACUAUAUUUAUCUUGUCAGUUUUUAUAUUUAAAGAAAGAAUACAUUGUAAAAAUGUCAGGAAAAGUAUGAUCAUCUAAUGAAAGCCAGUUACACCUCAGAAAAUAUGAUUCCAAAAAAAUUAAAACUACUAGUUUUUUUUCAGUGUGGAGGAUUUCUCAUUACUCUACAACAUUGUUUAUAUUUUUUCUAUUCAAUAAAAAGCCCUAAAACAACUAAAAUGAUUUGUAUACCCCACUGAAUUCAAGCUGAUUUAAAUUUAAAAUUUGGUAUAUGCUGAAGUCUGCCAAGGGUACAUUAUGGCCAUUUUUAAUUUACAGCUAAAAUAUUUUUUAAAAUGCAUUGCUGAGAAACGUUGCUUUCAUCAAACAAGAAUAAAUAUUUUUCAGAAGUUAUAGUUGUCUUUUAGUAUGUGAUACUAAUUAAGAUUACUUUUGUAUUAUCACUAUUUAAAAGAUCCUAGUAAUUUAUUCUUUCAAAUACCAUGUUAUUUGUUACCAUCACCGAUGAAUACCUCCUAGGCUUAUCCCUAAAAAUGCUCGCUCAGAGAAUUAAUUAUAAACUUGUUUUGUUUUUAGUAAGAAAUGGCUAAAGCUCUUUUUUUCCACAAUCGUUAGUAACUGUAUAAAAACUCAUGCUGCUCCACCAGUGGGCCUUGGAAAAUGCAUCAAGAAGGCCAAACCAGCUUGACCCUGGCUCACAGACAUGGUCAUGAGGCGAUUUAAAUUUGUGCCACAAUGAAGAGUGUGUGUACACAUGCCUCCUAGAAACUACACUAUGGGUAAUUAAUUAAUUUAUUUCAUAGAGGCCACCCAGAUGCCUUAUAGGUUUUAUUAAUUUGGAUAUGAAAGUGUACCCCAUUUGGUUUCACCAGGAACCCAAAUUUAGAAUAUUGAAAAGCCAUCAAAAAGUUGUGAUAUCAAAAAUGUAUGAGUCUCUUAAUAUACUAAGCAAGAGUGUCACAGCAGUAAUGAUAAAGACUAGUUUUAAUCUCAAGCCUUAGAGGGGCCCUUUGUUGCCUUUUGUGAUGCAGCCUCUUAAGAGAGUGGUGUUUGAUUAACAAAAAAACUGUGGCCCAAGUGGAACCCUUGACCUUUUCUCAGAUAAUCUGUGUAUGUACACAGCUAACACAGCUCUUUAGAUUCCCUGUUAAGUGACUCAUUCACAUUCCUUUCUUGGAUAUAAAGUCAUUGCUGUCUUUUUAUUUUUGAAAUAGUACAAGACAAAGAUUUUUAACUUAACAUGAAAAAUUCACUCUUUUAUUUUGGAAAAAAAGUUAACUUUUCAUACUAACAAACAGAACAAGAUUUAAGGUAAAUUUCUUAAACAUUAUCCAGAAAAAUAACAAGAUUUAUAGUAUCUACUUCUGGUACUAAUAUACACAAAAGGCCAAAACCAUGCCUAUUCUGCAGGUGUAGCUUCGGUGCUCUCCUGUUCAGGGGCAGGCUCACUGCCCGCUUCUUUUCCUUCUUUGCUUCUUUUAGAUUUUUUGUGUUUGUGUCUCCUGUGACUAUCUCCUUCUUCACUUUCAUGGCGACGUCUACUAUUAC